ACUAGCAGAGAAGCUGCUGUCCUUCCACCACCAGCACCGGACCACCUGCUCCAAGACCAGCCUCCUGGGGGGACCAGGCACCCGGCCUUCACUGGCACCCAGGGAGCCGUCCUCAGCAGCGUCAACAUGUCAAGGCCCAGCAGCAGAGCCAUUUACUUGCACCGGAAGGAGUACUCCCAGAACCUCACCUCAGAGCCCACCCUCCUGCAGCACAGGGUGGAGCACGCCUGUGGUCCACCUCUCUGAGCUUUCUCCCAGUCCUAGGACUCCCCCUCUCCCUGCAGCACUUGAUGACAUGCAAGCAGGGGAGUCAGAGAGUCCAGGGGCCCGAGGAUGCCUUGCAGAAGCUGUUCGAGAUGGAUGCACAGGGCCGGGUGUGGAGCCAAGACUUGAUCCUGCAGGUCAGGGACGGCUGGCUGCAGCUGCUGGACAUUGAGACCAAGGAGGAGCUGGACUCUUACCGCCUAGACAGCAUCCAGGCCAUGAAUGUGGCGCUCAACACAUGUUCCUACAACUCCAUCCUGUCCAUCACCGUGCAGGAGCCGGGCCUGCCAGGCACUAGCACUCUGCUCUUCCAGUGCCAGGAAGUGGGGGCAGAGCGACUGAAGACCAGCCUGCAGAAGGCUCUGGAGGAAGAGCUGGAGCAAAGCAGACCUCGACUUGGAGGCCUUCAGCCAGGCCAGGACAGAUGGAGGGGGCCUGCUAUGGAAAGGCCGCUCCCUAUGGAGCAGGCACGCUAUCUGGAGCCGGGGAUCCCUCCAGAACAGCCCCACCAGAGGACCCUAGAGCACAGUCCAUGGUCCCCUUACACUGCAGGCCUCCCACCAUCCCCAAGGCCCCUGCCACGCCACACCAGUGCCCGAGAACCAAGUGCCUUUACUCUGCCUCCUCCAAGGCGGUCCUCUUCCCCCGAGGACCCAGAGAGGGACGAGGAAGUGCUGAACCAUGUCCUAAGGGACAUUGAGCUGUUCAUGGGAAAGCUGGAGAAGGCCCAGGCAAAGACCAGCAGGAAGAAGAAAUUUGGGAAAAAAAACAAGGACCAGGGAGGUCUCACCCAGGCACAGUACAUUGACUGCUUCCAGAAGAUCAAGCACAGCUUCAACCUCCUGGGAAGGCUGGCCACCUGGCUGAAGGAGACAAGUGCCCCUGAGCUCGUACACAUCCUCUUCAAGUCCCUGAACUUCAUCCUGGCCAGGUGCCCUGAGGCUGGCCUAGCAGCCCAAGUGAUCUCACCCCUCCUCACCCCUAAAGCUAUCAACCUGCUACAGUCCUGUCUAAGCCCACCUGAGAGUAACCUUUGGAUGGGGUUGGGCCCAGCCUGGACCACUAGCCGGGCCGACUGGACAGGCGAUGAGCCCCUGCCCUACCAACCCACAUUCUCAGAUGACUGGCAACUUCCAGAGCCCUCCAGCCAAGCACCCUUAGGAUACCAGGACCCUGUUUCCCUUCGGCGGGGAAGUCAUAGGUUAGGGAGCACCUCACACUUUCCUCAGGAGAAGACACACAACCAUGACCCUCAGCCUGGGGACCCCAACUCCAGGCCCUCCAGCCCCAAACCUGCCCAGCCAGCCCUGAAAAUGCAAGUCUUGUACGAGUUUGAAGCUAGGAACCCACGGGAACUGACUGUGGUCCAGGGAGAGAAGCUGGAGGUUCUGGACCACAGCAAGCGGUGGUGGCUGGUGAAGAAUGAGGCGGGACGGAGCGGCUACAUUCCAAGCAACAUCCUGGAGCCCCUACAGCCGGGGACCCCUGGGACCCAGGGCCAGUCACCCUCUCGGGUUCCAAUGCUUCGACUUAGCUCGAGGCCUGAAGAGGUCACAGACUGGCUGCAGGCAGAGAACUUCUCCACUGCCACGGUGAGGACACUUGGGUCCCUGACGGGGAGCCAGCUACUUCGCAUAAGACCUGGGGAGCUACAGAUGCUAUGUCCACAGGAGGCCCCACGAAUCCUGUCCCGGCUGGAGGCUGUCAGAAGGAUGCUGGGGAUAAGCCCUUAGGCACCAGCUUAGACACCUCCAAGAACCAGGCCCCGCUGAUGCAAGAUGGCAGAUCUGAUACCCAUUAGAGCCCCGAGAAUUCCUCUUCUGGAUCCCAGUUUGCAGCAAACCCCACACCCCAGCUCACACAGCAAAAACAAUGGACAGGCCCAGAGGCUGAAGCAAACAGUGUCCCUUCUGGCUGUGUUGGAGCCUCCCCAGUAACCACCUAUUUAUUUUACCUCUUUCCCAAACCUGGAGCAUUUAUGCCUAGGCUUGUCAAGAAUCUGUUCAGUCCCUCUCCUUCUCAAUAAAAGCAUCUUCAAGCUUGU